AUGGAGACUGGGGAGCGCGCCCGUCUCAUCCUCAUCCUUGUCCUCCAGCUUCUCCUUCGCAUCCGACGCAACCGGCAGCAGCGCUGCCGCCGCGUCCUCAGCCACCGCUCCCUCUUCCCACGGAUGUGA